CCCGACCAGAUCCCGUGGUUCUGAGGACCGGCCCUGGAACCCUGCGUCCUUCCGACCCACCAGCUCCCUCGAGGAUGGACUUGAGGCUGGAUGCUUUCCUCUUCCCACUUUUUGUCCCAACAGAAGUCCCUGAUCUCCAGGAUCCCUGACUGGCUGUGCAGAGCUGGCACAGCCACACUCCACGGGCUUCCAGCCCUUCAGGCCCAGCUCUCCCGGAGAGCACCAGAGUCCCUUUGCUCCAUUUACUUGCGCUCUUCAGCCAGCAAGUGUUUCCUAAUGUCUCACCCCCAGUCCCAGCUUUCCUGCUGCAAUUUCCGCCUGUUCCCUCCCAUUUCAGGCCUUAAGGGAGUGUGGCUGGGCUUCUCUCCUCCCCCUCACUCCAAAGCCGCACUUGAUACAAGGUGGAAAUCAAAGCACCACUUCUGGCUUCCCAGCCUUGAACUUGCCCUUCCCUCUCAAUGUAUCUGGUUUCCUCAGCUUCCCUGUGCAGCAAGAGUGUCACUCCCCUCUUGCUUUUCCCAAGCUCCCCAUGCGCCCCUCUCAGCAGAUCUGUCUUAGAGGGGCCAGGUGCAGAGAAAGGCAGAAAUCCUAAUAAUGUUCCCAGCGAUCGCUGCCUGUCGCGGAGUGCUGAAGGGCCAAGUGUUGAUCUGAGUCCUCAUCACACGGGACUUCAUUUAGUCUCACGAUAGCUCCCAGGAAGGACCCUGUUGCUAGUGUGGAGCAAAGACGAGUCAAGUUUAUGGGCUGGAAGUCCUACCCGGAGGCUGCUCACUGAGCUGUGAUGGCUACAAGGACAGAUGGGGGGAAGGGUGCAGGGUGCCCGAGACCUGGCCCGCUGGAGCCUGUCACCUAAUGGCUGGCUGGAAGACCACUACACACCAGCCAGCCCUGGUCCAUUCUCUCAUUUAGAGGCCUCCCCGGUGGAGGCAGGGAUACACAAAAUGCUUUGGGGCUGGAUGGGCCCGCCUUUCAGUCUAAACAAGAGACCUCAACACAGCUGCCCAGAAAAGGCAGAUACCAGAAAUGGAUAAAGCUGGCUGGGUGGGGACUGUCCGAAGGGCAGCCAGCAGUGAGCUCCGGCUGGUUGCUACCACACAGGACAUAUGUGUUGCCAGACCUGAAUUUUCAAUAGAAACCAAAGAUAGUUUUUUAUAUAAAUGUUUAAUUGGCAAUUAAUUGAAAAAUUCUGUGUAUCAGCGAACAUGAUACAGCCCACAGCCUGCGGGUCUGCGCCCCUGGAUUAACAUGCUGCCCUGCCAGGAGGACACGACCUGCAGCCCCAUCCUAACUCUGGCCACCCCAUCCUGCAGGCAUGCCGGCUGCCGCUCCAGGACUCCCCUGUCCCCAGGACCAAGAUGACGCCCAACAGCACUGGCGAGGUGCCCAGCCCCAUUCCCAAGGGGGCUUUGGGGCUCUCCCUGGCCCUGGCAAGCCUCAUCAUCACCGCGAACCUGCUCCUAGCCCUGGGCAUCGCCUGGGACCGCCGCCUGCGCAGCCCACCUGCUGGCUGCUUCUUCCUGAGCCUACUGCUGGCUGGGCUGCUCACGGGUCUGGCAUUGCCCACAUUGCCAGGGCUGUGGAACCAGAGUCGCCGGGGUUACUGGUCCUGCCUCCUCGUCUACUUGGCUCCCAACUUCUCCUUCCUCUCCCUGCUUGCCAACCUCUUGCUGGUGCACGGGGAGCGCUACAUGGCAGUCCUGAGGCCACUCCAGCCCCCUGGGAGCAUUCGGCUGGCCCUGCUCCUCACCUGGGCUGGUCCCCUGCUCUUUGCCAGUCUGCCCGCUCUGGGGUGGAACCACUGGACCCCUGGUGCCAACUGCAGCUCCCAGGCUAUCUUCCCAGCCCCCUACCUGUACCUCGAAGUCUAUGGGCUCCUGCUGCCCGCCGUGGGUGCUGCUGCCUUCCUCUCUGUCCGCGUGCUGGCCACUGCCCACCGCCAGCUGCAGGACAUCUGCCGGCUGGAGCGGGCAGUGUGCCGCGAUGAGCCCUCCGCCCUGGCCCGGGCCCUUACCUGGAGGCAGGCAAGGGCACAGGCUGGAGCCAUGCUGCUCUUCGGGCUGUGCUGGGGGCCCUACGUGGCCACACUGCUCCUCUCAGUCCUGGCCUAUGAGCAGCGCCCGCCACUGGGGCCUGGGACACUGUUGUCCCUCCUCUCCCUAGGAAGUGCCAGUGCAGCGGCAGUGCCCGUAGCCAUGGGGCUGGGCGAUCAGCGCUACACAGCCCCCUGGAGGGCAGCCGCCCAAAGGUGCCUGCAGGGGCUGUGGGGAAGAGCCUCCCGGGACAGUCCCGGCCCCAGCAUUGCCUACCACCCAAGCAGCCAAAGCAGUGUCGACCUGGACUUGAACUAAAGGAAGGGCCUCUGCUGACUCCUACCAGAGCAUCCGUCCAGCUCAGCCAUCCAGCCUGUCUCUACCGGGCCCCACUUCUCUGGAUCAGAGACCCUGCCUCUGUUUGACCCCGCACUGACUGAAUAAAGCUCCUCUGGCCGUUUA